GUUCAACGCCGUUGGCGAAGCCAGCUGCUGGAGGUGCCGAGAAUCUGAGUUUCGGCAAGCAGCCAGGUCUGGAAACUAAUAUUUUAAAAAUGACUACACCAAACAAGACACCUCCUGGUGCUGACCCCAAGCAGUUGGAAAGGACUGGAACAGUACGGGAAAUUGGGUCACAAGCUGUUUGGUCACUCUCAUCUUGCAAACCAGGAUUUGGAGUGGAUCAGUUACGAGAUGACAAUCUAGAAACUUAUUGGCAAUCAGAUGGUUCCCAGCCUCAUUUAGUGAACAUCCAAUUCAGAAGAAAAACAACAGUGAAGACAUUAUGUAUUUAUGCAGACUACAAAUCUGAUGAAAGCUAUACUCCAAGCAAGAUCUCAGUCAGAGUAGGAAAUAAUUUUCACAACCUUCAAGAAAUUCGGCCUCAUGUUUUACAUGUGAAUGAAGAAUCAAUGAAUCUUCAAGUCUCAGGAUAAAGGAAUGAGAAUAUUGAAGCAGAAACUGCAAAUAAAAGACAAUGCAUACUUUUCUGUGUCCAUUUCUCCUUCAUAAAGGAAUUAAGAGAAUUCUUCCUACAAGGAUUUGUAGAUAUUUGGGAAUCUUUCCUCUUGUAUUUGAAAUUAUAGUUGAUGGUACAAAACAGAAACCGUAGCUUAGCCAUCUCACCACUUUUUUAGAAUCUGUUGCCUACUUUGUAAUUAGAUAGCUAAUUAAUAAUGAUAAUUAGCUAAUUGGAUGGCCUACAGCUAGUCUUGAUUUCUUAUACUUAAUUAAGUAGGACAGAGGCAGUACGUAGAGGAAGCUUUCUAAGCACUUACCAUGAGAAAAGAUCUAGAUUUAGACUAAGUGGUACCAUAAGUAUGAGGCAAUAGUAGGGAAAUUGUUCAGAUAAUAUGUUAGCUAUCUAUUUUAAUCUUUAUUGAGCCUAAAGUCUUUAGAUUUAAUCUUGUUCCAAAUUAACAUGUUUCCUGAGUAGCUAUGUGAAUUUUCUGUUACUUAUUUUUGAUAAUGAAAAGAUUAAAUUCUUGUUCUGGUUCUUAUAUAUCUCCUAAGUUCCCAUUCUUUGCCACUACAUAAACAAAACAUAAGGGCAAGUCCCUCAUAUUGAAAAUAUAUAAUCUUCUCUGAAUCUUCUUCCUCAUCAGUCAGGAUAAGGUUUCUUAGGGUUUGCCUGGCACACUUAGCUAAAAUAAUAAUAGUAUUUAUAGUACACUGGCAACUGCUGUUUUUCCUACUUCUUCCCUGAGACUGUAUAUAUGCUGCUAAAGAAAUGUGAUUUUUAUAAUAAAUGAGUAUCCCUUUUUUUUUUUUUUUUGAGACAGAGUCUCGCUCUGUUGCCCAGGCAGGAGUGCAGUGGUGCAAUCUCGGCUCACUGCAACCUUCGCCUCCCAGGUUCAAGCGCUUCUCCUGUCUCAGCCUCCCGAGUAGCUGGGAUUACAGGUGUGCACCACCACACCUGGCUAAUUUUUGAGACGGGUUUUCACUGUGUUACCCAGGAUGGUCUCAAUCUCCGGACCAUGUGAUCUGUGCCCGCCUGAGCCUCGCAAAAUGCUGGGAUUAUAGGCAUGAGCCACCGCACCCAGCCCCCGAUAUUUUUUUUAAAUAGGAAAACCUCCCUAAUUUUACAAUAGAAAUCAAUAUAGUUAUUUAUAAUUGAAACUUAUAACCAGUAACAACAAAAAUACUAUUUUAUUGUAUUAGUAUAUCUAUUUUAUCUGUGAGAACAACUAAAAUUAGAAAAUACGCGGAUUCCACCUCUGUAAACUGGUUAGGCUAGUGUUAUUUUACUAAUUUUUAAAUUUAGUUUUUUAAAUUGACAGAAAAUUGUGUAUAUUUAUGGUGCUUAUAAUGAUGUUUUGAUAUUUUUAUACAUUGUAGACUGACUAAAUCAAGCUAAUUAACAUAGGUAAUACCUCACAUAUAUGUCAUUCUUUGUGGUGUGAACGCUUAAAUCUGUCUUAGCAAUUUUCAAGUAUACAAUAUAUUAUUAUUAAUUGUACUCAUAGUGAUGCACAGUAGAUGACUUGAACUUAUUUCUUAUGCCUCACCGAAAUUUUAUGUCCUUCGACCAACAUCUCCCAACUGUCCCCCUUACUCCCAGCCCCAGGUAACCAUCAUCCUACUCCCUGCUUCUGUGAGUUCAACUUUAGAUUCCGUGUAUAAAUGAGAAGAUGCAGUUCUUUUUUCACUCCAAUUUUUUAAAAUGUUACUUAAAAUCAUAUUUUCUUUAACAUACAGUUUUUCAAUUUUGUAGGAGUUAACCUAAGUAAUCAGACUAUGUGAAAUCCUCUGAGGUUGACUAAAAGGUACUCUGCGAUUAUUUAAUAGAUAGUGUCCUUAGACUAAAUUAAAUUUUUCAGGAAAAUUAUAAUAUUCUUCAAAGUCCUGUUGGCUCCUUCUCUCAUUUCACUUAAUUAUGGUGAAUCUGGCCAAUCCAUAUAUAUAGUUUAUAUAGAAUGUCUCUUUACAAUAACUGUAUGCAAUAAUAACUAUGUGGCUGUUGGCUUAUUCCUCUAACUGCAUGAAUUUUUCAUGAAUUCUUUGAGAUUCAUGAAAAAAAAGAAUAGUUCUUUAAAAAUUACUGCAUCCAUUUUCAUUGUAUACUAAGUACUAUACAGGCCUACCUCAUUUUAUGCUUUUCACCUUAUUGCACUUUAUAGAUAACUGCAUUUUAUUACAAAUUGAAGCUUUGUGGCAACUGUGUCAAGGAAGUCUAUUGGCACCAUUUUUUUUAACAGCUUGUGCUCAAUUCCUGUUUCUAUCACAUUUUGGUAAUUCUCACAAUAUUUCAAACCUUUUCAUUAUUAUUAUAUCUUUUAUGGUGAUCUGUGAUCGGUGAUUCUUAAUGAUACUAUUGUAAUUGUUUUGGGACGCCAUGAACCAUGCUCAUAUAAUAUAGCAAACUUAAUUGGUAAAUAUUGUGUUCUGACUACUCCACCAACUGGCUGCUUUUUUAUCUCUUUCUCUCUAAUUGUGUUUUCCUGUUCCCUGAGACACAACAAUAUUGAAAUUAGGCCAGUUAAUAACCUAAUUAAUUGGCUUGAUUCAAUUAGGCCUCUAACUAAUGAUGAUGGUCUCUAACUAUUUAAGUGAAAGGAAGAGUUUCACAUCUCUCACUUUAACUCAACAGCCAGAAAGAAUUAAGCUUAAUGAAGAAGGCAUGUUGAAAGCCAAGAUAUGCUGAAAACUAGGCCUCUUGCUCCAAACAGCGAAGUUGUGAAUAUAAGGGAAAAGUUCCUGACGGAAAUUAAACGUGCUACUCUAGUGAACACAUGAAUAAUAAGAAAGCAAUACAGCCUUAUUACUGAUAUGGAGAAAGUUUGAGUAGCCUAGAUGGAAGAUUAAACCAGCUACAACAUUCCCUUAAGCCAAAGCCUAAUCCACAGUAUGGUCCUAAUUCUCUUCAAUAUUAGGAAGGCUGAGAGAGGUGAGGAAGCUACAGAAGAAAAGCUUGAAACUAGCCGAGGUUGGUUCAUGAGGUUUCAGUGAAGAAGCCAUCUGCAUAACAUAAAAGAGCCAGGUGAAGCAGCAAGUGCUGAUGGAGGAGCUGUAGGAAGUUACCCAGAAGAUCUGGCUAAAAUAGUUGAUGAGGGUAGAUACACCAAGCAACACAUUUUCAAUGUAGACAAAAAGCCUUCUACUGGAAGAUGCCAGCUAAGAUUAGAGAGGAGAAGUCAAUGCCUGGCUUGAAAGCUUCACAGGACAGGCUGGCUCUUUUGUUAGGGGCUGAUGCAGCUAGUGACUUCAAGUUGAAGGCAGCCCUCACUAUUCUAAUAAUCCUAGGGUCCUUAAGAAUUAUGCUAAAUUUAUUCUGCCCAUGUGCUAUAAAUGGAAGAACAAAGCCUGGAUGACAGCACAUCUGUUUAGAGCAUGGGUUCCUGAAUAUUUUAAUCCCACUGUAAAGACCUACUGCUCAGAGAAAAAGAUUUAUUUCAAAACACUAUGCUUGUUGACAAUGGACAUAGUCACCCAAGAGCUUUGAUGGAGAUGUACAAGGAGGUAACACAACAUGUAUUCUGCAGCCCAUGGAUCAAGGAAUAAUUUUGACUUCCAAGUCUUAUACAUUUCUUUAGGCAUUAGCUGCCAUAAAUAGUGGCAAAUGAUCUGAUGGAUCUAGGCAAAGCAAAUUGAAAAUCUUCUGGAAAUAACUUACCAUUCUAGAUGUUACUGAGAAUAUUUGUGAUUCACAUGAAAAGGUCAAAAUAUGAACAUUAACAUUAGUUUGGAAGAAGUUGAUUCCAAGCCUCAUGAAUAACUUUGAGGGUCUGAAGGCUUCAUUGGAGGGAGUAACUGCAGAUGUAGUGGAAACAGCAAGAUAACUACCAUUAGAAAUGGAGCCUGAAGGUCAGGUGCAUUUUGGGAGCCUGAGGUGGAAGAAUCUCUUGAUCCCAGGAGCUCAAGACCAGCCUGGGCAACAUAACAAGACCCCCAUCUCUACAAAAGAAAUUCAAAAAAAUUAACUGAGUGUGGUGAUGCACAUCUGUAGUCCCAUCUACUUGGGAGGCUGAGGUGGGAGGAUUGCUUAAGCCUAGGUGGCGGCGGUUCCAGUGAGCCAUGAUCAUGCCAUUGCACUUCAGCAUGGGCUACAGAGAGAGACCCUAUCUCAAAAAAACAAAAAGAAAUGGAGCCUGAAGAUGCGACCAAAUUGCAGCAAUCUCAUUAUAAAACUUGAACAGGUGAAGAGUUGCUUCUCAUAAAUGAGCUAAGAAAGUAGUUUUUAGUGUGUGAAGGUGCUGUGAACAUUCUUGAAAUGACAACAAAGAAUUUAGAAUAUUGCAUCAUCUUAGUUGAUAAAAGAAGACUGACUCCAAUUUUAAAAGAACUUCUACUGUCAGCAAAAUGCUAUUAAGUGGCAUUGCAUGCUACAGAGAAUAUUUUUCAUGAAAGGAAUAUUGAAUAAAUGAGGUAAACUUCAGUGUUAUUUUAAGAAAUUGCUUCAGCCACCUCAGCCUUUAGUAACUACCACCUUAAUCUGUCAGUAGCCGUCAUCAUUAAGGUGAGAUACUCUGCCUCCAAAAAAAAUUACAACUUGUUGAAGGAUCAGGGGAUUGUUAGCAAUUUUUAGCAGUAAAAUAUUUUUUUGUGAGGAUAUGUACAUUGUUCUUUAGACAUAAUGCUAUUACACACUUAAUAGACUACAGUAGAGUGUGAGCAUAAUAUAUGCACUGAGAAACCAAAACAUUGUAUGACUGACUCACUUUAUUGUGAUACUCACUUUAUUGCUGUGGUCUGGAACCAGACCCACAAUGUAUCUGGGAUAUGCCUGUACUUAUUUUAGAUAUAAUUGCUAAAACUUUAAAACUUUAUCUCAAAGUUGUAUUUUCCUAUUUAUAAAUUAGAGCAAAGAGGUAUUACACACAAAACUUGCAUAAGAAAUAACUGAGAUACUGAUAGUUUCAGUUAUUCCUGUAUCUUUGGACUAUUCCUCCAAUGGUUGAAUUUCCUUUUUUUUUUUAAAUUGGGGCUGCUUGAAAAACAUACAUGUUCUUUAGCAAUUUUGAAUAUUAUUCUUUGGCAGCAUUGUUUUAGAAAAUUGUUUUCAUAGAAUUUCUUCUUAGUAUCCAUGGACCUAUAUUGAGGGAGGUGGUUGGGGGAGAAAUAUGUCAGCGCUGUCAACUACCAGUAGAUGGUAUUAGUAGUUGCUUCUAUAGUUAAAAAUCGACACAUGUGAUUAAGUAGACUUAAUGAUGACCCUUUGGAAAUGAAUCUGUAAGUAGAAGAAUCUCUAUACUGUGUCAGAACCAGUAAUGAUACCCACUUCGUGUUGACUGUCAGGAAGCUUAGAACCAAAUUUGUGACCCAUGUGGUAACAAUUGUAUAUAUUUAUUUCUAUACACUAAUCUUGGCCCUCAGUUAUUUAUUUUGUCAUAUUAUGGCAUAUUUCUUUUCAGGGCCCACAAAUCUUUGAUGGCUUUGGUUAGCACAAGGACAUUACCUGUCUUGAUCAUCUUGAUCACUCAUGUAGCUGAGUACCUACCACAUAGGUGCUCAGUUAAUAUUUGUGCAAUUUAUUUCUGCAGUGGCCUUUGAUAUUUAUUUUAAAGAUAGUGGAGGGGCGUCCGUUUUAGCUUUACUGAGGAAAAGAAUCCAAGGCAGAUUAGUUCUAAAAUUGAUUCGACUCUAGCAGCCUACUUUCUGAUAUAAGCAUGUGAUCUUAGAGAAGAUAAUAAUGACUAAAGGGAAUGUAAUAUAGCUUUGGGGAAUAUAGGGCAAUCCUAAUUUGCCUCUUAUCAUAGCCCAGAGGUUAUGAGCUCUGGCUAAAUAUGAUAAGCAAGGUACUUUAGGGAAUAAAGAGAGACUGAGGAAUGAGAAGAAAUCUCUUUCUGCCUUCACUGUUCUACCUUAGUAUUUAGGUAGCCACUUCACAUUUAAGAUAAUAAAAGGGUAAAAGUUGAGUCAAAGUUACUGUCAGCCAGUUUGUAAAAUCUAGUUGAACAAUAAUCUCAUCAAUUUAAAAAUUUUAUCAUUUCUCUGAGGAAAUUUAAUGAAAGGCAUUGAGAAGUGUUCCUGACUUUAAGAAACUUAUUGUGAAUGAAGAGUUGCCUUGUGUUGAGAGGGAAUUGUCUCUGAGGAAAUUUAAUGAAAGGCAUUGAGAAGUGUUCCUGACUUUGAGAAACUUAUUUUGAAUGAAGAUUUGCCUUGUGUUGAGAGGGAAUUGUCUAAGGCAGAUAUGGAAUUCAAAUUUGAAACUUUUCUGUUGACCAGGUUCAGGAUUAUCGGUAGCAUGGAAUUAUCAUGACUCACUGAACUCCAUUUAACCUGAAGUUAUAGUCAUUUGAAACUUGCUGAUAUUCCCCCAGAGUCAUAUUGUACUCGCCAUUGAACGCAGAGUUCUCUAACCUUGGCUUACAGACGGAAAAACCCAGUCUGUUUCAUAACCUGCAAUCUGGGUUUUAAAUAUUGUUUUCAGAGUAGGACAGAAGGGUGAGACCUAAGCCAAAUAAAGGAACAUGUUUCUAGAUUGUCUUUGCCACAUGCUGCUUUAAUCAUGGGGUUUGGAGCCUGUCAGAUCAGAGUUGGAAUCUUGGUAUUAUCACUUCCUUGAGAGAGAGUACAAUUUCUCUGUUUUUUCUGAGCCUCUGUUUAUUUACUUUAAAAAAUGAAAAUUACAAUGCCUGUCUUGUUUGGGUGGUUGUGAAAAUUAGAUAAGCAGUGUAAAAACAUCUACCAUGAACCUAAUAUGUAUAGAUUCUUAGUCAAUAUAACUUUACGCCCAUCCAUACUACUUUUCUCUGUUAGCUUUGUAAUGGCUGCUUGCUUUAUCCUUACUCGUACAUGACUGUACAAGGUUGGAAAGUGCUAGAUAAAUGUGUCUUAUGUAUAUUAAGACAUGCUCAAGUUAUGGAAAAUGGAUAGGUUGUCUUGGAUUCAAUUCCUUACUAUCAGAUCUAAGCAUGAAGUGUUUUUUUUAAGGUUGAUAUUUGGCAUUUCGAUAUCAGUGUUUUCUCUGUUGCAACUGGACAGAGAGAACAACCUAUGUAGGUUAUUUGGAUUUUUAAAAAAAUUAUUUUAAUGAAAUUUCCCCUGGCAUUCGAGUAGAUAUACAGAUUUAAUUCUUUGAAACUACAGCAUCAGUGGCAUUAUUUUUUGUGGCAUAUGUAAAGCAAGAAUUUAGCAAUUUUAAGCUUCCUAGUAUUUAGCUAAUAACUUCACAUACUGGAGCACAUCUUUAUCCGUUGUGUCAAAAUAUUAGAUAUUUUCUAAGGUAAUAGUUUUACUAACGUGGAUACUUCCUUUGAUUUUGUUCUCUGUUCUUGAAAUUGUUUGUGCUUAUGGAAUUUAUUUUGUUAUAUUUAAAAAAGUAAAGCUGACUUUAUAAUAUGGAUGACUUUGAAUUUUACUUCUUAGCCCUUAUACUUUCUAUGCAGGAUGUAUUUUUAAAAAGAAAUACAAUAUUUACAGGAACAAAUUUAUAGAGUAGGGAGUAUAAAUGGGCAUUUUAAAAGUUAUUUAUAUACAUCUUAACUGCCAUGACUUUUAGCCAAGCCAGUAUUUUCAAGAAAGCGCUGUCUAUCCUAAUUGCACAAAUAUUUUUGCAGACUUUUCCAUUAAGCAGUGAAUGAAGCCCUGAAAGUCACUGUAGCCAAUGUGAAGGCAGAGGAUUUGAGAGUAGUAAUGGAUUUUUAGAAAUGCUUAGGGUGCGCUCCUGUAACAGGGCAUUUGCUUUUAGGGCAGUUUGGCCCAACAAUUGAACAAAUUAGUUAUGUUUGAAAAUUUAUAAAGCAAAAGCAUAGAUAAUCAUAAUAUAAUUUUUGCUAGAACAUAUGUUAAGUUGGCUUAUUAGAUCAGAUCGUUUUUUAAAAUUACAGUAUGAAAAAGUUAUUCAACUUAUUUUAAAAAUUCUUCUUUGCAAAGAAAUUGAUACCUUGAUACCCAUGGCAUUAAGACAGCUUUUUACUUCUUUGUGGGCUGGCAUAAUGGACAGACAGUACUUUAGCCUUGGAAAUCAGGAGUAUUGACGUGUGACAUUUUAGAUGAGUAUGUGUGUAUGUGAACAGGUACAUGUGGAUGCAAGCAUGUGUGUAGAAGAUCACGUAUACAUUCAUAUAUGUGAGAGUGCAUUUGGGUUAGAAGUGAUAUGAAAAAAAGUGGAGUAUUGUAUCUUAGUAAACUUUUACUUCAUUAAUCUCCUUCAAGUUGUUGAUCAUUAAUAAUUGGAUAUUCUUUUGUAGAAUGGCUUUGGAACUUGGCAGUAUUCUGUAAUCCAGUUUUACAAGAUGACAUGGGGAGAUGACCAGGGAAUUUACUCAUAUUUUUUUUAGGCCGAGUGAUGUUGAUAGACCACAGUUUGGCAAAGUAGACAGAUCUGGUUUCAGAUCUUAGUUUUGCUACUUACUAGCUGUGUGAAUCUUGGAGAUAUAUUUGGCUCUUUUGAAACCUCAGUUUCCUCAUAUAUAGAAUAGGUGAACAAUGUCUGUCUUAUUGGAUUCCAGAAAGAAUUAAGUAGGAUAAAGUUUGCAAAGUACUUAUUCACAUUACCUGGUCACAUAGUAAACAGUCAGUUAAUGCAAAUUCUCUUUUUGGGUGUGUUUUUAAAAAAAUAAAUAAUAUUUUACAACUUAAGCCUUUUUUGAAUAUUUGAAGUAAAAUGCAAAUUUAUUUUUACAUUAGCUUUUGGAGAGUAUUAGUGCUUUCUGCAUCUUGGGAGAAAUCUUAUUCUUUUAUUUAGUUGUAUAAACAUAUAAGCAAAAGUAGGCAUAAUAGCUGAUUAUUGUUUUAAAAAAAAACUUCCGAAUGUUUAUAGUGAACUUCUAUAAAAUGAAAAUUACUCUGUGCAACUUAUGUGGCAUAAUUUACAAAUCAGUUCAAUUUGGGGAAAAUAUAAUUUAUAUCAAAUAAUAUACCACCAAUUUGGGGGAAAUUAUAUUACUAUAGUGUAAUAUAAUUAUAGUGUGUUAUUAACUAUAGUGUGUCACUAAGAUAAACUAAAAAGCCCAUUAGUUAGCCAGUAUUGUCAUGUUUCUGAGGUUAAUUGGCUGCAUUCAGUUAUAGGUUAUGAACGGUACCACUUGAAUGAUCCACCAAGCUAUCAGGCAGAAAGACCAAUAGUUCACAAGACUAAUUGACCCUGUCAGUAUAAUAGAAACACUUACAAAUAAAAUUCUCUUUGCAAACAACAUUGCGAAUGAAAACCCCAGAAGAAACUGUUAUGUCCUGUAACUGUCCUGGAAUGCUAUGAUUCAGUUAGCAGACUGUGGGUGGAGGUGGGUCAUGGUGGGUGGGAGUUGGGGGGAAGGAAAUGCAAAGGAUAGAAAGGAGAAUUUUGGAGGGAAAUUAAUCAGACAAAACGUUAGAGAGAAACACACAUUUUUUGAAAUGAUUUUAACCUUCUUGAAUCUCUAAAAAGUACUGUCUUUAAAUUUUUCAUUUUUUUACCCUUGUUCUGUAUCUUAAGCCCUUUUGUUAGAUUUGAUAGUCAUUGUUGCAUUGAGCUCUUUUCUGAAAGGUAAGAACGUAUUUUUGUCAAACACAUUGCUAUAAUGAGUAUGAUGUGUGGCUGCCAUUCUUCAGUCUUUCUUCAUUUACAUGUAUCAUCAAUAUAAUGCAAAUACUGUCAAGGGCAGCAUUAUCUCCUUGAAUCUAUUUUUUGUUUUGUUUUUUAGUAUAGGUUUGUAUUUGUGCUGGUGCAGGAGGAAGGGGGAAAGUGUUGGGAAGAAACAUAGAAAGAGAGAAAGAACAUUUACUUUCUAACAAAUUUUGACAAUUUGUUUUUCUCUUUUUUUGGUAAUGAUCAAAAUUAUAUAUUAAAGAACUUCCCAAAGCAAUAUAUCAGCUUUUAUUAAAGAAAGCAAGUAUUUUCAAAUGCUUUAAGAAACUUGGUGAACUCUAGUAUAAGGGUUUGGUUUUCAAAGGGAAAAAAAAGAAUUUUAUCUGGAAACAUUUUAGGUAAUAUGGAUCCUCCAGUUAAUCUAUGGGAAAUUAUGCAGCAGAUAUCAGCCUUCAUUUGUAAUACUGUAGGAGGGUGAUAACUUUCCUGUUGCAUUUUCUUUUUGUAAAAGACAUCUUUUACUUUGUCAGAAAACAACAGUCAAGUUGUAAAUGGUCUUCAAAAAUAGUAAUAAAAAAAGAUUUAUAAUGGAAAGAAUUGAUGGUAUAUUUCACCUAAAGUAAGAAAGACAAUGUGUAAUAAGGGAUUUUGCGGUUUUACAGCUCAGUGCAUGUGUUUGAAAGCUGUUCUCUCAGCAACGUGGGUGGCAGGUUAUGCUACCAUAUAAUGUAUUGUAGUUGGCUCUCCACACUUGUCAGGGUUAGUGUUCAACCAUUCGGAAAAUUUUCCCAUUGUUCUAUCAUGUGAACCAAGACUAGUGUAGAAUUCCCAAUAACUUACAAAAAAAGGAUUAAUUAGAAAGUUUGAAAUUUGAUUACUUAUUGUUUUAAUACAGUACUAUGUAUUUUAGUAUUUUAUCUAUAAUUAGAAUUGUUUUUUAGUCAAAAUAAUGUAUCAAAAUCAAAACUUCAUCUUAUUUUUUAAUAGAUUUUACAGAAAUUUGUAUACUGAAUCCUGCCUCUUUUUUUUGUAUUAACACUGUUUCCAUCUUAAGCAUUUUGCUUUAGAUGGACCAUAGCUCUUGGCAGCUAGUGCAUUUUUAGCAAAUAAUACUGUUUCUAGUAAGAGUUGCAGAGAAAAAAAAAAACUUUGUGUGAGGUCCUUGUAAACUGAACCUUUGGAACAUUACUUUAUUUCUUUUUUCCCCUCUUUUGUGCUUCUUCGCUAUUUGUGUAAUGGUUAUAAAUUACAUCGUUUGAAAAGAAGAAUUAAAAACACUUUAUUUUGUUUUUUUUUUAGACAAUUUUUUCUUUACCUGUUAUUUUAAAGAUGUACAGAGAAAUAAGCAGUUAGGGUAUUGAAAUUCCAUUGUGCCAGCACCUCCAGAGCAUAAUCCAAAAAAAACAGAAAACCGCCUGCUGGGUUGUCUGCAGUAUGCUUGUGUGAACAUCAGUGUCUGCUGUUCACACAUCAUUUUUUUUUUACUGAAAGUUCCUCUUGGAAUAAAGACUCUGUGUUUUCUGAGUGUAGUGAAACAUUUGUUGGUUCUUAUAUUUUUCAAUUUGUGAGGGAUUCUGUUUAUAGGAUAAGUUGUCAUGGCUAUAUGUUGCACUAAUGUUAUUGGCACAUCAAAAAAGUAGAGAAAAGGCUUGUGUAUUUAUAUACUAUAAAAUAAUGAAAAAAUGAAAUUAGAAAGUAUUGAAGGUGAGAAAUUUUGUUGAAGAUAUAUGUGAAGAAGGAUUGAUUUAAAUAUUGAUGUUUGCCCUUUAAAAUCUAUUUUAUUUAUAAAGUAUAUCUUGGCUGGAUUAUACAUCUGAAAAUAUCAUAAAUGUCUUGUAUUUCACUUGGAAUUCAGAUUCUUAAGUAUGUUGGCUUCUUGAUAGUAUUGUUAUGAGUUAGUCAAAUUUUUCAACUGACCCUACAUAAUCAAGGAACGUUCAGGAAGUAUAUUUAUGGGUGCUUAGAAUAAUUUUUAAUUUUUGAUUAUGUUUCAUAUCAUUUAUUUUUACUCUUAUGCUACUGAGUAUCACGUUAGAUACAGGCAGCAAACUUGUGAAAUGUAGUCUAGUGUGUUGGCAGUCUCAACCUUCAUUCAGAUUCAUACAGCAUCAAAACAAAAAAUUAUUUACCAGAUAAUAGGGAACUUAAGGUUAAAAUUUGGUAAAAUGGAUGUUGUGAUCCACAGUCUCCCCAAAGGUUUAUUGGAAUUAUUCAACAUUUUUUGUUUUUAACUUUCUAUAUAGAAGUUAAUAAAGGAAUAAAUAUACAUAUCUGAAACUGGGUUUUUACCAUUUUGACUAUUUUUUAUAAAGAUAUAAUUUCAGGUUUGUUUGUCUCUGAAUUUCACUCUGAGUUUCUUGAUCAAAAUUCAGAUGCACGUUUACAUUUCAUAAUUGUUGUAUGAAUCUUUUAAUUAUUGUUUCUUGUGGUUAUUUAGGAUAAUAUUGCUGUAUAUCUGGAACCAGUUAUUAAAUUUUAGUCAAUAGAUCCAAUAGUCAAUGAAUGAUUCUUGCUCCUCAAUUUGCUUCUUAUUAGUUGUCUUAUUCUCUCACUGAAUCCAGAAUAUGGAAGAGAUUGUCAUCUAAGCAAGACAUAUCUUGCAUAUGCCUUCUAGAAGGGGAAGUGAAAGCACCAAGUCCUUAAUGUGUCAGUUUUCUAAGGGCCUACGAUGUCUGAGUUUCUUGAUUGCCAAGAAGCCUAAUUCUUCACAGGGCAACCUGGCAUACAGCCAUUUCCACACUGGGCUGUUCGUUGGUACUUGUGAAUAGAACAAAAACGGUCUUUGCUUUUUCUCCUCAGUUAUCAAUGAUUAUCAUUUUUGGAAACAAGUUAAAACAUUUUUCUCAAAAUGAUGAUUAUUCAUGUCAAGAUGAAGUCAAACUUCAUGCUAUCUAAGCUGUAAGUAAUAGAGUUAGUUCAGUAUUUUAAAAAUUCAUGUAAAAUAAAAUUUGUUACUUCUCACUCCAAAAUAUUCAUUUUGUAAAAUUUCACCUUAACUAUUGUUAGACAGAUGUUCUAGAUUUAGCUAAACACUUUUGAAAGUAAAUUAUGAGGUGGGUUUUUGGCUAAUUUUUAUACUUCUAUAAGUAAAAUCUGUUAUAUAUGAAUUAUGGGACCACUAGAAGUCAUAGAUCCUACAAGCAAAGUGUUUGUGGGUCAUUGGGUUGGGGAGCUACUUCAGUUGUUUUUUUUAAUAUAACUGGAGGUGUAUAUUGGAUUUUUACCUCUGCGUAGAUCUGUAGUAAGAACUUUGUUCCCAUUGUCAUGCAUUAUUUCUGUGCAUAUUAACUAAUAAUAUAAAACAAUAAGUAUUAUGAGACUUUCACCCAGUUGAAUUAGUUUCUUCCUUCUCAGUCCCCUUCAAAGUUCCACAUCUCUUUAUAGCAUAUGUAGAAUUAUGGCUUUUUGAGUUGUCGGUAUUUAUUCACUUGUACUUAUCUUAGAAUAUGUUCUUUUAUUUUUAUUCUAGGCAUACAUACAUACUUUAAGGUUAUUACUUCGGUGAUGUUCAGGAUUUUGGUUGGGUAAUUACUUUCAAAUCCUGGCUAGCUAGGUCACUAGCUAGGUGACCCUUGGGCAGAUUGUAUAACCUUUCUAUGAACUUCAGUUACCUAUAAAUUAACUAUAAAUUGGAGAUAUGAUGUUGGGAUGAUUGCAACAAAUGUUUUAAGUGCCUGGAACAUACUAGCAGCUCAGUGAAUGGUAGCUGAAAGGAGCAAAGCCAUUAAAAUUUGUUAUGUUUUUAUAGGUCUUAAAAGCAUACAAUAGGCUGGGCAUGGUGGCCCACGCCUGUAAUCCCAGCACUUUGGGAGGCCAAGGCGGGUGGAUCACCUGAGGUCAGGAGUUCGAGACCAGCCUGACCAACAUGGAGAAACCCCGUCUCUAUUAACAAUACAAAAUUAGCUGGGUGUGGUGGCACAUGCCUGUAUCCUAGCUACUCAGGAGGCUGAGGCAGGAGAAUCGUUUGAACCUGGGAGGCAGAGGUGCGGUGAGCCCAGAUCGUGCCAUUGUACUCCAGCCCGGGCAUCAAGAGCAAAACUCCGUCUCAAAACACACACACACACACACACACACACACACACACAUACACACACACUAAAACAAAAGCAUACAAUAGUUUGCUUUUCUAUAUAAUCUCAUGAAAUUAAGAGUUUUCAUUACAUCUAACUGUUUAUUUCUUUGGGUUGUUAAAGAUCCAAGAGCAUGGGCUUUGGAGUCAUCUGCUGGAGUUUGAAUUCUUGCUCUGCCAUUUAACCAUGAACCUUGGAAUGUUAGCCUCAGAUUUCUAGUAUCUAAAGUGAAGAUUAAAAGAAUGUACCUUGGCUGAGUACAGUGACUUACGCCUGUAAUUCCAGCACUUUGGGAAGUCAUGGCAGGCAGAUCACAAGGUCAAGAGAUCGAGACCAUCCUGGCCAACAUGGUGAAACCACGUCUCUACUGAAAAAUACAAAAAUUAGGUGGGUGUGGUGGUGCGUGCCUGUAGUCCUAGCUACUCAGGAGGCUAAGGCAGGAGAAUUGCUUGAAUCCGGGAGGUGGAGGUUGCAGUGCUCCAAGAUCUAGCCACUGCACUCCAGCCAGGCGACAGAGCGAGACUGUGUUUCAAACAAAAAAAAAAGAGUAUACCUCAUAGGGCUAUUGCAAGGCUGGAAAAAAAUCAAUACAUCUAUAGUUCUUACAACUGUGCUUGCCAAAGAAAAAGUGCUUCCAAAAUGUUUAUUGUUAUUUAUUAUUAUCUCAUAGAAAAGGAAAAAUCUAAAGCAAGAAAACUUGAAUGGAGUCAGCCUUAAUCAUGUCUCUUUCAUCCACUCCUAUAUAAUUCACACUACUUUUCUUCCCAAUCUCUUUCAGAAUUCCACAUUUCCACAAAGCAUAUUUAGAUUAUAUUGAAGUCAGAAUUGUGCAUCUUAUUCAUUACCUACAUAGGAUUGCGAUAACCUUGCAGUAAGAAUCGCUUAGCUGUGGAAUUCUAGUUUGAAAAUAAUUUUCCUUAGAAUUUUAAACACAUUUUCCACUUCCUCAUUGUUUUUAUUGUAAAUGUUGAGAAAUACAAUGCCACUUUUGAUUUCUGAUGCUUUGCAUGUGACCUAUUUUUCUCUGUAGAAAGUGAUGUCUCGUCAUCAGAAGUAUCUGUUGAAUUUGUUGCCUGCUUCUUAUAGGUUUUGCCUUAGUUAGCCUUUUUUUUUUUUUUUUUUUUUUUUUUUUUUGAGACAUUGUUUUUAUUGUAAAUGUUGAGAAAUACAAUGCCACUUUUGAUUUCUGAUGCUUUGCAUGUGACCUAUUUUUCUCUGUAGAAAGUGAUGUCUCGUCAUCAGAAGUAUCUGUUGAAUUUGUUGCCUGCUUCUUAUAGGUUUUGCCUUAGUUAGCCUUUUUUUUUUUUUUUUUUUUUUUUUUUUGAGACAGAGUCUCACUCUGUCUCCCAGGCUGGAGUGCAGUGGUGCGAUCUUGGCUCACUGCAACCUUGGCCUCCCAGGUUAAAGCGAUUCUCCUGCCUCAGCCUCUUGAGUAGCUGAGAUUACAGGCAUUCACCACCACACCCAGCUAAUUUUUACUAUUUUUAAUAGAGACAGGGUUGCAUCAUGUUAGGCUGGUCUCGAACUCCUGACCUCAAAUGAUCCUCCUGCCUUGGCCUCCCAAAAUGCUGGGAUUACAGGCAUGAGCCAUUGCGCCUGGCUGCCUUAGCUUUUUUCUUCUUUUUUUUCUUUGAGACGGAGUCUCACUCUGUCAUCCAGGGUGGAGUGUAGUGGCACCAUCUCGGCACUCUGCAACUUCUGCCUCCUGGGUUCAAGCAGUUCUCCUGCCUCAGUCUCCCCAGUAGCUGGGAUUACAGGCGUGCACCACCAUGCCUGGCUAAUUUUUGUAUUUUUAAUAGAGACGGGGUUUUGCCAUGUUGGCCAGGCUGGUCUUGAACUCCUGACUUCAGGCAAUCCACCUACCUUGGCCUCCCAAAGUGCGAGGAUUAUAGACAUGAACCACCAUGCCCGGCCCUAGUUAGCUUUUUAACCGUCCUUUUGAAUGACCUUUUAUCUAUUAUUUAUUUUUAUUUUGUAGAGAUAGGGUCUCACUAUGUUGCCAGGCUUGUCUGGAACUUCUGGCCUCAAGCUAUCCUCCCCUUUACGCCUCCUAAAAUGUUGAGAUUACAGGCGUGAACCACCAGGCCCAGUCAUAAAAUGGCCUUUUAAAGGCUUCAUUGUUAUCAGUUGUUUAAAAGGUAGGUUGGUGUCCAUGUAUCUUUCUGCUUCAACUGGAUUUUUUUUUUUUUUUUUUUUUUGAGACAGGGUUUUGCUCUGUCACCCAUGCUUGAGUGCAGUAGCGCAAUCAUGGUUCACUGGGGCCUAGACCUUCUAGGUUCAAUCGAUCCUCCUGCCUCAGCCUCCUGAGUAGCUGAGACUACUGGCAUAUGCUACCAUGCUCUGCUAAUUUUUGUGUUUUUUGUAGAGACAGGGUUUUGCCAUAUUGGCCAGGCUGCUCUGAAACUCCUGGGCUCCAGGGAUCUGCCUGCCUUGGCCUCCGAAAGACAUGGGAUUAUAGGUGUGAGCCAUUGUGCCUCGCCUUCAUCUGGAUUUUUAAAUAAGCAAUUGUUUACUUAAUAGUUAAAUGAUUUAUAUAAAAAGUGUUUUAUAGUGACUUUUUGGCAUUUUGAAUUUAUGAUGCCCCCACCUGUUUCUCAGUGGGUUGUAAUCCAGUGGCAUGAUAUCAAAUAGCCUGUUUUCUUAGAUAUAUUUCUGACACGUUUACUUAAAGGCUAGUUUUAACCUUUCUUUCUUUUCAAUAUUUAUUUACUGUUAAAAUUUAUGGUGAUAGGGCUGGGUGUAGUGACUCAUGCCAGCAUAAUAAAACAUUUAAAAAAUUAUGGUAAUAGAAUGAUAGUGUACUUUUUAAUUUAAAAAUUACUCAUACAUGUGAACAGUCUAAAUUUCUAUAUGUUUGCAUAAGAUUUUCUCAUACCUGCCAUACAUACAAUUCUGUUUCAUUUUUGUUCUAAGAUAAAAGAUACGUUUCAAUAUCAUGUAGCAGCAAAUCGUGAUGUUACCUGGAGUAUGAAGGACUUGGAAAAAACUAAACCUCAUGGAUAGCAUGAGGAGCUCCGCAACUGUGUUCUGGAGUUUCUGUUGGGUCCUUAGUGUUUCCCUGCUCUCCAGAGUCCAUAAAACACACAUUCAUGCAUGCACACACAUACACACACACACACACACACACACACACACACACACACACACACGUUAUCUAUUUGGUAUAAGAAAUAGAACAUUAUGAGUAUCUCAGUUCCUGUCACAAACCUUCCCCUACCCUUUAGGGAAAACUAUGAUCCUUCCUUUUUAUGUUAACUUUCUUAAUUGUCUUUAUAGUUUUACCACUGUGAAUAUGUACCUCAGCAUUAAUUGAGUGCUUGUUUUUGAACUCGAAGUAGUUUAGACUUGGUAUUGUUAAGUUUCUGCCUUUCUUUUUUUGUUUUGCUAACUUACUAAGUCAUAGUUUUUUAUUUUCAGUUAUACUAACUUUGAGUUUUUGUAAUUUAAUGUUUCUUUUUACUACAGUAAAACAUGUAUGUAGGUUAAAAGCGUGAAAGAGCUGGGUAUGAUGGCAUAUGCUUAUAGUACCAGCUACUUGGGAGGUGAAGCAGAAGGAUUGCUUGAGCCCAGGAGUUCAAGGCCAGCUUGGACAACAUAGUAAGACCCCAAUCUCUUAAAAAAAAUAGUGUGAAAUAUUUGCAGUAGCACUUGCAACAAUCAUACUUCUCACCCUGUCCCACACUCUUGCCUCACUCUUUGGGAGCAAUCCUGUUAGCUAUGUUAGCCAAUUUUUGUUAAAAAAUUGUAGAAAUAUUUACUUUCAUAUUUCUAAAUGCAUGUACGUAGAUACCUGUAUUAGAUGUGUACAAUUCUAAAUAACGUGUACGUAUCUAUAUUUAAAGCUGUGAUCUAAUCAUAUCUGCUAUAACACAUCAGGAUUUAGCUCUAUAAUCCCAUUCCUUCUCUCAUCUACUUCCCUUAUCUUCAUCUUACUAGUGUAGGUUUUUGUGGUAUUUGCUGAAAUCAUUAUGCAUGUUUUCAUUAUUAUGAUCGCAUAAGUAUUUUUAUGCCUGAAUCAUACCAUGUCCUAAUGCUUAAAUUUUUUUUAGGCAUUAUUUUGUUUUCCUGGAAUUAAUACUUUACCUUGUUUCUUAAUUUUUAAAAUGUUGGUUACCAACAUAUGUCUAAAUUCUCUGACAGAUUAUAAACUCUUUCUUGAAACAGCAAUACGUAACUCUCAGUUCCACAUUUUUUCUGGGUAACAUCCCUCCUGGACUUCCAGCUCAUCUGCUACCAGUGGAAGGUCCAUCAGAAAAGCAGAGAGUGCUGAGGAAGACCAGGGGUGUAUAGUAAGGGAUUUACUACAGGGAUUUUACCUUUCCCAAGUAGAAGUUGGUUAAAUAAAUUCUGUAAGACUGUUGUUUUCACAUCUGAUGUAAACAGAUGAGCGUGAAGUCCAUAGGGCAGGAAGUUGAAAGUGAAGAUUUAUGUAAAGUGGUGGGGAACAAAAACAAUCUGGAACCUAUGAGCACAGGCUGGAACCCAUGAAGAUGAACUGGAAUCAUUCAUGUUCACUGCCUCCAAUCUUGUGACAAGUGUCCUGCAGAAGAAGUUGAUUUCUUUUUUCUUAGAGCUAAACACUCACCUGACCUAGGAGUUGGAGAGCCUGCAGGAAGAUCUAAGGGAAUGAGGGUCAGUUGUAGGCCUGGCUCCUGCCCCAUGACAAUGGUGUGAAGCAGUAGAUAAUGACAAUGUAUAUGAUCUAUAAAAGCGCCUGCUUGUCUUGAAUGUAAAAAUAAAAUGGCUGCUGCCUCUCUUUUGCUCUCCAAAA